AGGCCCCGGGGAUUGUGGCGUGACCCGGCAGCGGCUUCCUCCGUUCGGGCAUCGCUGUGCCUCGGGUUCGCGCCCCGAGUGAGCAGUCCUGGCCCGGAGCGUCGGUCCUGGUAAUCUGUAGGAAAAGCGCUGCGGCCCAGGGGGUAAAGAGAGAUCAGCCUCUGUGGACUCGGUGCUUCUCCUGGCAAGUAAACCCCAAGGAGGACUGACCAGUUCUUGAAUUUCUAUACCAUGGCCCUUCGAUCAGUGAUGUUCAGUGAUGUAUCCAUAGACUUCUCUCCAGAAGAGUGGGAAUACCUGGACUUGGAACAAAAGGACUUGUACAGAGAUGUCAUGUUGGAGAACUACAGCAACUUGGUCUCACUGGCAGGAUGCUUCAUUUCUAAACCAGAUGUGAUUUCCUCAUUGGAGCAAGGAAAAGAGCCUUGGAAAGUUGUGAGGAAAGGAAGAAGACAAUAUCCAGAUUUGGAGACCAAGUAUGAGACCAAGAAGUUAUCUUUAGAAAAUGACAUUUAUGAAAUAAAUUUAUCCCAGUGGAAGAUAAUGGAAAGAAUUGAAAACCAUGGCCUUAAGGGUCUCAUUUUAAAAAAUGAUUGGGAAUCCACAGGAAAAAUUGAAGGACAGGAGAGACCUCAAGAAGGAUACUUCAGUAGUGUGAAAAUGCCAUCUGAAAAGGUGUCCUCUUACCAGAAACGCACAUCUGUUACUCCACAUCAGAGACUUCAUUUUGUUGAUAAACCCUAUGAAUGUAAGGAAUGUGGGAAGGCGUUCAGAGUGCGCCAACAGCUUACUUUUCAUCACAGAAUUCAUACUGGUGAAAAACCGUAUGAAUGUAAGGAAUGUGGGAUGGCCUUCAGACAGACUGCACACCUUACUCGACAUCAGAGACUUCAUUCUGGUGAAAAACUCUAUGAAUGUAAGGAAUGUGGGGAAGCUUUCAUAUGUGGUGCAGAUCUUAGAGUACAUCAGAAAAUGCAUAUUGGUGAGAAGCCCUAUGAAUGUAAAGAAUGUGGGAAGGCUUUUAGGGUACGAGGACAACUUACUCUGCAUCAGAGGAUUCAUACUGGUGAGAAACCCUAUGUGUGUAAAGAGUGUGGAAAAGCCUUUAGACAGUACGCACACCUGACUCGGCAUCAGAAGCUUAAUAGUGCUGACAGGCUCUAUGAAUGCAAAGAAUGUGGGAAGGCCUUUUUGUGUGGCUCUGGUCUUAGAGUACAUCACAAACUUCAUACUGGUGAGAAACCCUAUGAAUGUAAGGAAUGCGGGAAGGCCUUUAGAGUGCGACAACAACUAACACUCCAUCAGAGAAUUCAUACUGGUGAGAAACCCUAUGAAUGUAAGGAAUGUGGAAAGACCUUUAGCCGUGGUUAUCAUCUUAUUCUCCAUCACAGAAUUCAUACUGGUGAAAAACCUUACGAAUGUAAGGAAUGCUGGAAAGCCUUUAGUCGCUACUCACAACUUAUUUCACAUCAGAGUAUUCAUAUUGGUGUUAAGCCCUAUGACUGUAAGGAAUGCGGGAAGGCCUUCAGACUACUUUCACAACUCACACAGCAUCAGAGUAUUCAUAUUGGUGAGAAACCUUAUAAAUGUAAGGAAUGUGGCAAGGCCUUUAGAUUGCGCCAAAAACUUACUCUACAUCAGAGCAUUCAUACUGGCGAAAAACCCUUUGAGUGUAAGGAAUGUAGGAAGGCCUUUAGACUUAAUUCAUCCCUUAUUCAACAUCUGAGAAUUCAUUCUGGUGAGAAACCCUAUGAAUGUAAGGAAUGUAAGAAGGCCUUUAGGCAACAUUCACACCUUACUCAUCAUCUGAAAAUUCAUAAUGUAAAAAUCUAAGAAAGUCUUUUCAACUUCUGUGUUAUAGAACAUUCUAUGAAUGUAGUAAUUAAUCUAUUUUGCUCCAUACAUGCAACUGCGUUGGCAUUAGAGGUUUUAUACCAUUAAAAGAGUGUGACAAUGUAUUGUAGUCCAUCAUCACUCAAACCUGAAACUUCAGCAUAUUUGUUCUAAAAACUAAUCCUGUUAUAAGAAUGAAAAAGACAUUUACCGUCAUCCCUAUCCCAUCACUUUGUGUCAUACUGGACAAGACGCUUAACUGCUCUGUGCUAUAAUUUUUUAAUUUAUGACAUGGUCAUAUAAGAGUGCAGCAGUUUGACACACUUUCAAUCAAGAGGUGGAAUCUACAUCCCUCUGUUGUAUACAGGAAUCUACAUCCCUCUGUGACUGCUUCGCCCAGUAGAAUAUGGUAGACGUACUGCUGUGCUGGUUUCUUGACUCAGACUUUACUGGUAGGGUUACUUCAUCUCAUGAAAUGACAGAACUGUCUUGUUACAAAGUCUGGCUACUUUGCUGAAGAGACCACAUGAAGAGGCCCUGAAACUACGUAGAGAGGGAGAGGCACCUGCUGAACCCUGUCUUCUUGACAUCCACCAAGAUACCAGACAUUUGAGUGAAAUUUUGGAUCCACCAGACCAGCCACCAGCUAAAUGCCAGUGAGCGACUUGGUAACCUGAACUGAUGCCAUGUAGAAUGGAAGAAUUGACCAGCUGAGCCCCUGGCCCAAAUUUCUGACCCACAAAAACAUGAGAUAUAAUAAAAUGGUUGUUGUUUUAAGCCACUAAACUUUCUUUUAUUAUCAUACUAAAUAUUUAUUUUUACAUAAUUCAUACUAAAGGCUGUGGGCAUAAUGAGUAUAGAAAUGCCUUCCACCAACAUUUAAUCUUCAUUGAACUUGAGAUAUCUUAUUCUCGUUAAAAUAUUGAAAGUAAGGAAUUCCUUUCCAGUUUGUUCAUUAAAAAACAGAUACCCUAGACCAGGUGAGGUGGCCCAUGCCUGUAAAUCCAGCACUUUGGGAGGCCAAGUAAGGACGAUUGCUUGAGGCCAGAAGUUCGAGACCAGCCUGGGCAACAUGGUGAGACCCUGUCUCUACCAAAAAACUUUAAAAAUUAGCUGGGCAUAAUGGUGCAUGCCUGUAGUCCUAGCUACUCGAGGCUGAGGUGGGAGGAUCAUUUGAACCCAAGAGUUGAGGCUUCAGUGAGCUGUGAUUGUACCACUGCACUCCAGCUUGAGUGACUGCAAGACCCUGUCUCAAAAAAAAAAAAAAACUACAAUCAGUAUUCUCUGGCCCCAGUCAAUAUUAAAAAUUGACAAAGGAUAACAUGAAACUUUGGAAAUUAAAAGUCACCUGUAUUAUGAAGCCCCAUUAAUUUUUUAAACUACUUCAUUGUUUUUUAAAAAUGCUAAAUUGUCAAUUUAGCAUUUUGAGGCAAUCCCCUCAAAUUGGCUCCUGUGUCCUUUUAUCAUGACCACUCCAACCUUUGAGCUUUUUUUUUUCCUGAACCAAAUGCAUUGAUUAGUUAUGGAGCAUACUAGAGCAUUAUUAACAAAUAAAGGAAAAGAAUGGAAUAUUUACCUUGCCUAUCCUUUACAAACUAUAUUUCAAGACAACCAAAAGUUGGUGAAGGAAAGUUGUUGAUUAGAGAAUUCCAACUGGUUAAAAGGUCAAAGGAGGCCAGGCGCGGUGGCUCAAGCCUGUAAUCCCAGCACUUUGGGAGGCCGAGGCAGGUGGAUCGUGAGGUCAGGAGAUCAAGACCAUCCUGGCUAACACGGUGAAACCCCAUCUCUACUAAAAAUACAAAAAAUUCGCCGGGCGUGGUGGCAGGCGCCUGUAGUCCCAGCUACUCAGGAGGCUGAGGCAGGAGAAUGGCUUGAACCCGGGAGGCGGAGCUUGCAGUGAGCCGAGAUCGCGCCACUGCACUCCAGCCUGGGUGACAGACCGAGACUCUGUCUCAAACAAAAAACAAAAAACAAAACAAAACAAAGAUCAAAUGAAUGAUAGAAUUUGAAAACUACGCUCUUUAAUUUUACAAAAUCAUGGAUUUUCGUGGUGAUAGCAAUGGAUGCGAAGACCAUUAGGUGAAAAAUGGAUAGGAAGCUUAUAAUGCAUGGAGCAGAAUGACAGGACACUAAUCUAUAUUAACAUCUCUAAAUGAGAUCAGCCAGAUGAACUUGAUGUGAUGAAAUGGAUACACACAGUGGACACCUGUGAAGUUUUCUUGGCUCCCCCAAAACUGAGAAGUACAAGUUAGUCUCCAAACCUAAUUACCAGUUUACAGGAAACAUGGGGAAUAAAAGAACAAAUUAACAACACAAAGAAGCAAACAACCAAAUGCACAAUUUGGGAAAUUCUGCAGAAGUAAUGGCCUAGUUUUUUAACCAAUACAUGUCAAAAAAAAAAAAAAAAAAGACAAAAAUGGAAUCCUACACUUUAAAGGAGACUAAGAAACGUAUCCUUCAAAUACAGUGUAUGGAGCAUUUUAGGAUCCUUGUGUUAAAAUGCGCUUGGGAUUUGUUUUAAUCAAUCAUGGUGAGACAGGCAGACAUGGAAAUUAUUGUCAUGAAGGAAGAAGUUUAUACGCAGAUCCCACAAACGGGAGGCAUGGCAUGGCAUGCAGGGUCACGUAAAGAAGCACCUGGGUGUAUCAGGAGGCAGAGGGUGAGAGCACAGCAUGGCCCAGAGCUUUUAUUGGGGGUUUUCAUGGGAAGGAAUGGACAAGGCAGGGGUAGGCACACUGGUAAGCUUAGGAUUGAAUAGUUUGAGUAAUUUUGUUGGUCUCUGGGAUCUAGGGGGGAUUCGUAAUUGUCUAGUUAGGGCAGGGGAAUAUUGAAUUGGUGUAUGAGAGUUUGGUAAAGGAGAUAGUUGGGAGUAUGGGCUCUGGAUUGGUUGGUUUGUAUAUGAAAGGCAUGCUUGCAGUGGAGUUUAUCAUCUAUGCAUUAGCUUGCCCUGGGAGGGGCAGCCUAUCCAGGAUCAAGGCCCCAAGUGGCCAGAGCAUCAGGAAUACAGAAAAUAAAGAAAACAUAGUCAAUACAAGAUUUGAAGGAAUAAAAUGUCUCUACAUAUUGUACAAAUGUAAACAUGGAUUGGUUACUAAAUGAUACGAAAUAAUUUAUUGUUCAUAUGUUAGGCAUGACUAUGGCAUUAUGGGUAUAUGUGUAUGAGUCCUUAAGUGUUAGAGAUUCAUACUGAGGUAUUUAAGGCUGAAAUGUUAUGCCUGUGAUUUACUUUUAAAUACUUAAAAACAAAAGGUGGGAGGGAUAGAUGAAACAAGAUUAGCAAAAUGUUGGUAAAUGUUUAAUCUGGAUCAUUAGGUACACAGGGUUCAUUGUGCCGUUCUUACUAUCUUUACAUAUAUUUUAAAUUUUCCAUAAUAAAGUUUUUUAAAGUAGAAAAUCAAGUUUGGGCCAGGCGUGGUGGCUCAUGCCUGUAAUCGCAGUACUUUGGGAGGCCAAGGUGGGUGGAUCAUUUGAGGCCAGGAGAUCAAGACCAUCCUGGCCAACAUGGUGAAACUCUGUCUCUACUAAAAAUACAAAAAUUAGCUGGACAUGGUGGCACGCCUGUAGUCCCAGCUACUCGGGAGGCUGAGGCAGGAAAAUCGCUUGAACCCAGGAGGCGGAGGUUGCAGUGAGCUGAGAUCACACCACUGCACUCCAGCCUGGCAAUAGAGUGAGACUCCAUCUCAAAAAAAAAAAAAAAGAAAGAAAAUCAAGUCUGAAAUUGUAGACUAUUUAGUGAUGAAUGAUCACAUGUUGCCUACAGAUAACUUGGGGGAAAUCACCAACCAAAGCUCUACUUGGUAGAAAAUUUAAAGCAAUGCAUUUAGAACAUCUGGAUUGAGAAAUAAGUAUUUGUGUUGUUCACCAUUCUGUUCACACACCUACAGUGCCUGUCACAUAACAGGCAAUUUAUGGGAAAAAAUAAGGAUUAACUUAAGCUAGAAAUUUUUAAAAACUAAGGUGAAUAACAGCAAGUAGUUUAUAUGAUCAAAUAAAUUAAUGGAAUAGUUAAUAAAAUAACAGACUAAGGAUAUUCUCUUUGAAAAGAACAUUAAUAUAGAAUUGGCAGUUAUUGAGGGAAAAACAUGACUCACAGCUUUAUGUAUGGAAAAAG